GGCUGCUCCUUGCUAUAGAAGACCUGGGACAGAGGACUGCUGUCUGCCCUCUCUGGUCACCCUGCCUAGCUAGAGGAUCUGAGACUACUCACCCCAUAACCUCAAAAACCUCUUCAUGAGGAUGGUGACCCCAGCCAUGAGGACCCUCGCCAUCCUUGCUGCCAUUCUCCUGGUGGCCCUGCAGGCCCAGGCUGAGCCACUCCAGGCAAGAGCUGAUGAGGUUGCUGCAGCCCCGGAGCAGAUUGCAGCGGACAUCCCAGAAGUGGUUGUUUCCCUUGCAUGGGACGAAAGCUUGGCUCCAAAGCAUCCAGGCUCAAGGAAAAACAUGGCCUGCUAUUGCAGAAUACCAGCGUGCAUUGCAGGAGAACGUCGCUAUGGAACCUGCAUCUACCAGGGAAGACUCUGGGCAUUCUGCUGCUGAGCUUGCAGAAAAAGAAAAAUGAGCUCAAAAUUUGCUUUGAGAGCUACAGGGAAUUGCUAUUACUCCUGUACCUUCUGCUCAAUUUCCUUUCCUCAUCCCAAAUAAAUGCCUUGUUACAAGA